CCUUCCCAGGGUCCUCACCCUUGGGCCUCUUGGGGACUACCGAUGAGCCUCCUCCCUCAGGCCCCUCGACGACGCAAGGGGCCCAGGCUCCUCUCCUGCAGCAGCGCCCCCAGGAGCUGGGAGAGUUGAGGGUGCUGGGCAGAGAUGAGACAGGGCGCCUCCGUGUGGUCUGGACCGCCCAGCCUGACACCUUUGCCUACUUCCAACUGCGCAUGCGGGUGCCCGAGGGGCCGGGGGCACAUGAGGAAGUGCUGCCAGGGGACGUCCGCCAGGCUCUGGUGCCUCCACCCCCUCCUGGAACCCCGUAUGAGCUGUCACUUCAUGGGGUCCCUCCUGGGGGCAAGCCCUCUGACCCCAUCAUCUACCAAGGCAUUAUGGACAAGGAUGAGGAGAAGCCUGGGAAGUCCUCAGGCCCACCACGCCUGGGUGAGCUGACGGUGACAGACAGGACCUCCGACUCCUUGCUCCUGCGCUGGACGGUCCCCGAGGGCGAGUUUGACUCCUUCGUGAUCCAGUACAAAGACAGGGACGGGCAGCCCCAGGUGGUGCCCGUGGAAGGACCCCAGCGCUCGGCCGUCAUCACCUCCCUGGAUCCUGGCCGCAAGUACAAAUUUGUCCUGUAUGGGUUUGUUGGCAAGAAGAGGCAUGGUCCGCUGGUGGCUGAAGCCAAGAUCUUGCCUCAGAGUGACCCAAGUCCAGGGACUCCACCCCGCCUGGGAAACCUGUGGGUGACAGACCCUACCCCAGAUUCACUGCACCUCUCCUGGACUGUCCCUGAGGGCCAGUUUGACACCUUCAUGGUCCAGUACAGGGACAGGGAUGGACGGCCCCAGGUGGUACCUGUGGAAGGGCCCGAGCGUUCAUUUGUUGUCUCCUCACUGGACCCUGACCACAAGUACAGAUUCACUCUGUUUGGAAUUGCGAACAAGAAGCGGUAUGGCCCCCUCACGGCCGAUGGCACCACUGCUCCAGAGAGGAAAGAGGAGCCCCCCCGCCCUGAGUUCCUGGAGCAGCCCCUCCUGGGGGAACUGACAGUGACCGGCGUGACCCCAGACUCCUUGCGUCUCUCAUGGACAGUGGCCCAGGGCCCCUUCGACUCAUUCAUGGUCCAGUACAAGGAUGCACAGGGGCAGCCCCAGGCAGUGCCUGUUGCGGGGGAUGAGAAUGAGGUUACUGUCCCCGGCCUGGAUCCCGACCGGAAGUAUAAGAUGAACCUCUACGGGCUUCGUGGCAGGCAGCGUGUGGGGCCCGAGUCUGUGGUGGCCAAGACUGCUCCUCAGGAGGAUGUGGACGAGACCCCCAGCCCCACAGAACUGGGCACGGAGGCCCCGGAGUCCCCCGAGGAGCCGCUCCUGGGGGAGCUGACAGUGACAGGAUCCUCCCCUGAUUCGCUGAGCCUCUUCUGGACCGUCCCCCAGGGCAGCUUCGACUCUUUCACCGUGCAGUACAAGGACAGGGAUGGGCGGCCCCGGGCGGUGCGUGUUGGGGGCAAGGAGAGUGAGGUCACCGUGGGAGGCCUAGAGCCCGGGCACAAGUACAAGAUGCACCUGUACGGCCUCCACGAGGGGCAGCGCGUGGGCCCGGUGUCCGCCGUGGGCGUGACAGCCCCACAACAAGAAGAGACCCCUCCAGCCACUGAGUCCCCGCUGGAGCCACGCCUAGGAGAGCUGACAGUGACAGAUGUGACCCCCAACUCUGUGGGCCUCUCCUGGACAGUCCCCGAGGGCCAGUUUGACUCCUUCAUAGUCCAGUACAAGGACAAGGACGGGCAGCCCCAGGUGGUGCCGGUGGCGGCAGACCAGCGAGAGGUCACAGUCUACAACCUGGAGCCUGAGAGAAAAUAUAAGAUGAACAUGUAUGGACUACAUGAUGGGCAACGCAUGGGCCCCCUGUCUGUGGUCAUCGUGACGG